GAACGGGCCGCAACGGCCACCGCAGCUGCCUUCGGCGCCGCCAGCCCCGCCAUGGCUGCGCCCUGCGCGGAGGACCCCUCGCUGGAAAGGCAUUUUAAGGGCCACCGAGAUGCAGUUACCUGUGUGGACUUCAGUAUCAACACAAAGCAGCUGGCCAGUGGCUCCAUGGACUCAUGCCUCAUGGUCUGGCACAUGAAGCCGCAGUCACGCGCCUACCGCUUCACUGGCCACAAGGAUGCCGUCACCUGUGUGAACUUCUCUCCUUCGGGACACCUGCUUGCUUCCGGCUCCCGAGACAAGACUGUCCGCAUCUGGGUACCCAAUGUCAAAGGUGAGUCCACUGUGUUUCGUGCACACACAGCCACAGUGAGGAGUGUCCACUUCUGCAGUGAUGGCCAGUCCUUCGUGACAGCCUCUGACGACAAGACAGUCAAAGUGUGGGCAACUCAUCGCCAGAAAUUCCUGUUCUCCCUGAGCCAGCAUAUCAACUGGGUCCGCUGUGCCAAGUUCUCCCCCGACGGGCGGCUCAUCGUGUCUGCCAGUGAUGACAAGACUGUUAAGCUGUGGGACAAGAGCAGCCGGGAAUGUGUCCACUCGUAUUGUGAGCAUGGCGGCUUUGUCACCUAUGUGGACUUCCACCCCAGUGGGACGUGCAUUGCCGCUGCCGGCAUGGACAACACAGUGAAGGUGUGGGACGUGCGGACUCACCGGCUGCUGCAGCAUUAUCAGUUGCACAGUGCAGCAGUGAACGGGCUCUCUUUCCACCCGUCGGGAAACUACCUGAUCACAGCCUCCAGUGACUCAACCCUGAAGAUCCUGGACCUGAUGGAGGGCCGGCUGCUCUACACACUCCACGGGCAUCAGGGACCAGCCACCACUGUUGCCUUUUCAAGAACGGGGGAGUAUUUUGCUUCUGGAGGCUCUGAUGAACAAGUGAUAUGUGCACGACCCUAGACGCCAUCCAUCUGGGAGAGGAAACAGUGGAGCUGCUCAGACAGUGGUGAGGAGCCUCCUGAAGAACGAGGCUCACAGCUGCGUCCUGACAGACAGGGAUGGUGUCCAGGGCAUAUGGAGUGUUCAUCUUGUGUGGAUACGGUGGUUUUUCUGUGGCCUCAGGUGACCACUGGCCACACACUCCCCAGUUCUCUUGUGACACCCAAGCCAGCCAUCCUGGAAGUGGCCCUGGAAGCACACCGUCAUGCAUGGCCAGCAGCCUCCAGCAGGGAGCGCUCUUGCUCCCCAGCCAGGUGCCUCCCUCAGCUGUGUUCAAGGAACCGAGGGACAUGGUCCUGCUGAUAGGAGGACACCUGGAAUAGGAUGUGUUUUUCAUGGCUGAGUUAGCCUUGGGAUGACGAGUGUGUUGCUGAGUACUUCCUGUGUGCCCGUGUCCACCAGGCUGUCUCCUGUGAGCCUCACAGCAGCCCCAUGAGAUGGGAACUAGGCUUAUCCCAGUCUCGCAGAUGCAGGAACUGAGGCACAAGGUUGAGUCCCUUGCCUUAGGCCAUUCAGUAAGGAGUGUUCUGGCCUGGAGGCCAUGUGUUAACCACUUCUCACAGUGUAACAGGCCAGGCCACCGCCCGCAGGAACUUCUAUUUUAGUUCAGAGGCAGAUGAUAAACAAUGAAAAGGGGAUUAAAUAACUCCCUACUCUGAUGCUAUGAAGGAAAUAAAUAGAGGGCUAUGAUAAACAUUCACAGAAGGCCUCUCUGAGAAGGUGGUGCUGUUGAAGCAGACACUUCAGCCUGCGAAGCAGCCAACCCCAUGAAGCUCGGGCCUGUGACACCCUAGGGAGGUGAACCAGCAAGUGCGAAGGCCUGGCGGUGCCACGCCGUGGUAGUCCAUCCUGGUCACAUCCAGGUCCUCUUGAGGCCUGUCCACAAAGCCUGCUCCCCAGGGAGGUGGGGUAGGUCCCGGAAUUGAGUUGGGGUGUCAGGUGGGGACCACUAUCCCACCAUGGCUCAGAACUUUGGGCAUGGCCUCUGAGCCCAUUUCCUCAGUGAAGGACUGGCAAGGGGAUUUUCUUCUCCUGACUUGGUGUGCCUGUUGGUUUUGGCAGGUGAUGGUUUGGAAGAGUAACUUUGAUAUUGUUGAUCAUGGAGAAGUCACGAAAGUGCCGAGGCCCCCAGCCACACUGGCCAGCUCCAUGGGGAAUCUG